GCAUUCCUCGCGGCACCCGCGGACACCAGGCAGGCCCGGCCGGGUGCGCGGCCAAGGCCCGCUCCCCGCGUCCCCGGGCGCCGCCCCCGCCCGCGGCUGGGCUCCGAGAGACGAGUGGGAGAGCGAGUGCAGCGAGGGCGAGAGGCGAGCCGAGCAGGCCGCCCUGCCCGCGGCCCUAGCGCCGGCGCGAGGAGGGGGCGCCGCGGCCCACCCUCCUUCCUGCCUGGCCGCGGGCCGGCCGGGCCGCCGCGCCCCGACCCCCAUGGCCACCCAGGCCUCCGGGCCGCGAAGUCGCAGCGCCAGACCCAAGGCCCCCGAGUGAGCGCGGGCGCCGAGGCAAGCCGGUAUAUUCGGGGCCCAGGAGCAAGGAAAAGUGGCCUUUUGCGUGACACAGAAGUGGACACAUCAUUCUGAUCUCAGGGCAGGCUCAGCCCCAUAACUCUGGCAAAAGCUCUCACAAGCAAAAGCCUUGGAGAGGAGGAGAAUGUAUCAAGAGACAGGGGUCUUGCCAUGGCUGGUCUUGAAGUCCUGGGCUCAAGCGAUCCUCCCUCUUUGGCCUCCCAAAGUGCUGGGAUUACAGGAGUGAGUCACUGCACCCAGCCUUACUCCUCUUUAGACUCCCAAGCCUAGACCAAUUGCUUUCAAAUUCUUGCCCGUGACCUAUAGUAAGAAAUACAUCGUAGGUAACUACACAGGUCACACUGUAUAUAGCUGAAACAAAAGUUUACUGAAAUAACUCCCUUACUGUGUCUGCUGGUCUGUAAUCCUUUUUGUUCUUGUGUAUUUGUUUUUUUUUUAAUUACUGAUUGCUACCCACGAAAUUAAUUUUGCAAUCCACUGAUGGGUCAUACCCAGAAUUUGAAAAAAACAAGCCUAGGAAAUGAAUUUGCCAUCUAUUCAUGCAACAAAUGUUAAUUGCAACCCUAAUAAUUCCUCUCAUGUUAAACUACUCAAGUAACACUUGGAUACUUGGGUGAAAAAUGCAAAUAAGCCAGAAAUAUAUGUAGUAAAAGUAAAAGUUCCCUUGGCACCCUCCCUGCAGGUAACCCCAGUUAAUAGUUUGAACGUAUCCUUCCAGACUUUUUGUUACUCACUUAAUGCAUAUAUAUAUAUAUAUAUAUAUAUAUAUAUAUAUAUGUAUGUAUGUAUGUAUAUUACAUAUACCAAUCCAUGCAUAGUUUUCUUUUUCCCCAAGUGAGGACAUACUGUGGGCUCUUCCUCGGCAGCUUCCUUUUUCCUCUCCGUUUGUCUUGGAGAGGUUGGUUGUGUGGCGAAGUCCUUCAGGGCAAGUUCUGGGUUGACUCCUGGCUCCACCACAUACUGAACAGGCCAUUUACCUCUCUGUGCCUCAGUGUCCCCAUCUUUACAAUCAGGAGAAUAACAGUACAGACCUCACGGUACUGAAGUAAAGAUGCAGUGAGUUAAUCCAUAUGAAGUUUAGAGCAGUGCUUUUGCCAAUAAAUGCUGAUUGCUGCCGUCAUUGUUGUAUUGUUAUUGCUGUUCUAUCUCCAUGGCAGCCCAUGUUUGAAAUGCAUUGCUUUCCACAGCUGCCUGUGGCCAUGGCAUGGGUGUCUUUUUCCUCCCCUAUCCAACGUGUGGCUCCACAGGGAGGGAGGAGGUGCAACAGCAACGGUGUGCGCAGAGCAGCGUCUCUGCGGGAGAGGCACCUGGGCACUGGGCCCAAGGGAACAGGGAUUUUCCAAGGACCCACUGUUUCCAAAGUUCUGUGCUUAAUGUCGGGGUCCAAGCAGGAAGCAUCCCUGCACUUGACCACAAGAAGGUCACAGCCCAGUGGGUGAUUGGGACCCAGCUCAUAGCCAAGGCCUCGACCAGAGCUGGAGGCUUCCUGGAGGAGGGGCCUUUGAGCAGGUGCUUCAGGCACGGCGAGGUAAGAGUGAGAGGAGCAUUCCUGGCAGAGGGAACACAGUGAGCAGAGCGAGUCUUUGGAAGCUGGAAGGGAUGUGGCCUGUGUGCUGUAGCCAAACAAGAGGGGAGGACUUGGCUCAGAAAGAAUGGUGGCGGAAGAGGUUGGGCUGUUGCUGGGACCUCCUCACUGGCCUCCCUGCCUCCAUCCUGUCCCCUCCCAGGUGCUGGCCAGCAGCACUGUCAGAGCGAUCGUUCUAAACCCAGCAGAUAACCUCCAGUGGCUCCUGCUGCCUUAUGAAUAAAGGUCCCAUCUGUAGUUCUUCCCAUGCUGUCCAGGGCCAUUUCUGGUGUCCUCUGCCUGCCCUGUCCUCAUUCAGUCCUGUCCCCUCCAGCCACAGCUGGCACCUCCUUGUUAAGGUGCAGCCAUGUGCAUCCUUGCCUCUGUGCAUCGGGCUGGGCUGUUCCUUCCACCUGGGAUGCCCCUCACCUUCCUCCCUGCCGCCCCAGACCAAAACAGACGUCCUGUCUCCUCCUCCUCUGACCUCCGAGGCAGAAUGAGUCAUCUCCCUUUGUCUAUACUCGUGGCAUAGCGUUUAUCACGGAAUUAUCGGCAAUUCUGCCAGUGUCUGUCCUCCCCAUGAGGCUGAAGCAUCGAGGCCUGAAAGCACGUCUCCUUGCUCUCUCCGGCCCAGUGCCAAGGGCGAGGCCUAGAACACAGGACGCUCAGAAAUGCUUCCUGGCAGGAGGGCCAGGAUCUCAUCUGGCCACCGCGUUCUGGAAGAGGCGAGAGGGAGAGCGUGCGCGAGAGGAGAGAGACGGCGGGGGAAAGGGAGACGGCGAGACGCGCAGCGCCGGCGCCCGGGAGACCCAGGAGGAGCCCGCAGAUAACCAGCCCGAGUCAUGCAGUCUUUUCGAGAAAGGUGUGGUUUCCAUGGCAAACAACAGAACUACCAGCAGACCUCGCAGGAAACAUCACGCCUAGAGAAUUACAGGCAGCCGAGUCAGGCCGGGCUAAGCUGCGACCGGCAGCGGCUGCUCGCCAAGGACUAUUAUAACCCGCAGCCUUACCCGAGCUAUGAGGGUGGCGCUGGCACGCCCUCUGGCACUGCAGCCGCGGUGGCCGCCGACAAGUACCACCGAGGCAGCAAGGCCCUGCCCACACAGCAAGGCCUGCAGGGGAGGCCGGCUUUCCCUGGCUACGGCGUCCAGGACAGCAGCCCCUACCCAGGCCGCUAUGCUGGUGAGGAGAGCCUUCAGGCUUGGGGGGCCCCACAGCCACCACCCCCACAGCCGCAGCCACUACCUGCAGGGGUGGCCAAGUAUGAUGAGAACUUGAUGAAAAAGACAGCAGUGCCCCCCAGCAGGCAGUAUGCAGAGCAGGGCGCCCAGGUGCCCUUUCGGACUCACUCCCUGCACGUCCAGCAGCCACCGCCGCCCCAGCAGCCCCUGGCAUACCCCAAGCUCCAAAGGCAGAAGCUGCAGAACGACAUUGCCUCCCCUCUGCCCUUCCCCCAGGGUACCCACUUUCCUCAGCAUUCCCAGUCCUUCCCCACCUCCUCCACCUACUCCUCCUCUGUCCAGGGUGGUGGGCAGGGGGCCCACUCCUAUAAGAGUUGCACAGCACCGACUGCCCAGCCCCAUGACAGGCCGCUGACUGCCAGCUCCAGCCUGGCCCCGGGGCAGCGGGUCCAGAAUCUUCAUGCCUACCAGUCGGGCCGCCUCAGCUAUGACCAGCAGCAGCAGCAGCAGCAGCAGCAGCAGCAGCAGCAGCAAGCCCUUCAGAGCCGGCACCAUGCCCAGGAAACCCUCCAUUACCAAAACCUCGCCAAGUAUCAGCACUACGGGCAGCAAGGCCAGGGCUACUGCCAGCCGGACGCAGCCGUCCGGACCCCAGAGCAGUACUACCAGACCUUCAGCCCCAGCUCCAGCCACUCACCCGCCCGCUCCGUGGGCCGCUCACCUUCCUACAGUUCCACACCGUCGCCGCUGAUGCCAAACCUGGAGAACUUUCCCUACAGCCAGCAGCCGCUCAGCACCGGGGCCUUCCCCGCAGGGAUCACUGACCACAGCCACUUCAUGCCCCUGCUCAAUCCCUCCCCAACGGAUGCCACCAGCUCUGUGGACACCCAGGCUGGCAACUGCAAGCCCCUUCAGAAGGACAAGCUCCCUGAGAACCUGCUGUCGGAUCUCAGCCUGCAGAGCCUCACGGCGCUGACCUCACAGGUGGAGAACAUCUCCAACACCGUCCAGCAGCUGCUGCUCUCCAAGGCUGCUGUGCCGCAGAAGAAAGGUGUCAAGAACCUCGUGUCCAGGACCCCAGAGCAGCAUAAAAGCCAGCACUGCAGCCCCGAAGGGAGCGGCUACUCAGCCGAGCCCGCAGGCACACCGCUGUCAGAGCCGCCGAGCAGCACGCCACAGUCCACGCAUGCGGAGCCGCAGGAGGCCGACUACCUGAGCGGCUCCGAGGACCCACUGGAGCGCAGCUUCCUCUACUGCAACCAGGCCCGUGGCAGCCCUGCCAGGGUCAACAGCAACUCGAAGGCCAAGCCCGAGUCCGUGUCCACCUGUUCUGUGACCUCUCCUGACGACAUGUCCACCAAAUCUGACGACUCCUUCCAGAGCCUACACGGCAGUCUGCCGCUCGACAGCUUCUCCAAGUUCGUGGCGGGUGAGCGGGACUGUCCGCGGCUGCUGCUCAGCGCCCUGGCACAGGAGGACCUGGCCUCCGAGAUCCUGGGGCUGCAGGAAGCCAUCGGUGAGAAGGCCGACAAAGCUUGGGCUGAAGCACCCAGCCUGGUCAAGGACAGCAGCAAGCCACCCUUCUCGCUGGAGAACCACAGCGCCUGCCUGGACUCUGUGGCCAAGAGUGCGUGGCCCCGGCCUGGGGAGCCGGAGGCCCUGCCCGACUCCUUGCAGCUGGACAAGGGCGGCAAUGCCAAGGACUUCAGCCCAGGGCUGUUUGAAGACCCUUCCGUGGCCUUCGCUACGCCUGACCCCAAAAAGACAACUGGUCCUCUCUCCUUUGGUACCAAGCCCACCCUUGGGGUUCCUGCUCCAGACCCCACUACAGCAGCUUUUGACUGUUUCCCGGACACAACCGCUGCCAGCUCAGCGGACAGCGCCAACCCCUUUGCCUGGCCAGAGGAAAACCUGGGGGAUGCUUGUCCCAGGUGGGGAUUGCACCCUGGCGAGCUUACCAAGGGCCUGGAGCAGGGUGGGAAGGCCUCAGAUGGCAUCAGCAAAGGGGACACCCAUGAGGCUUCGGCCUGCCUGGGCUUCCAGGAGGAGGACCCCCCUGGGGAGAAGGUGGCCUCGUUGCCCGGGGACUUCAAGCAGGAGGAGGUGGGUGGGGUGAAGGAGGAGGCAGGUGGGCUGCUGCAGUGCCCCGAGGUGGCCAAGGCUGACCGGUGGCUGGAGGACAGCCGGCACUGCUGUUCCACCGCCGACUUCGGGGACCUCCCACUGCUGCCACCCACCAGCAGGAAGGAGGACCUGGAAGCUGAGGAGGAGUACUCCUCCCUAUGUGAGCUCCUGGGCAGCCCCGAGCAGAGGCCUGGCAUGCAGGACCCGCUGUCACCCAAGGCCCCACUCAUCUGCACCAAGGAGGAGGUGGAGGAGGUGCUGGACUCCAAGGCCGGCUGGGGCUCUCCGUGCCACCUCUCAGGGGAGUCCGUCAUCCUGCUGGGCCCUACAGUGGGCACCGAGUCAAAGGUCCAGAGCUGGUUUGAGUCCUCUCUGUCACACAUGAAGCCAGGUGAAGAGGGGCCUGAUGGGGAGCGAGCUCCAGGGGAUUCCACCACCUCGGACGCCUCUCUGGCCCAGAAGCCCAACAAGCCUGCUGUGCCCGAGGCGCCCAUCGCAAAGAAAGAGCCUGUGCCACGGGGCAAAAGCUUACGGAGCCGUCGGGUGCACCGGGGGCUGCCCGAGGCCGAGGACUCCCCAUGCAGGGCACCAGUGCUGCCCAAAGACCUCUUGCUCCCUGAAUCCUGCACAGGGCCCCCCCAGGGACAGAUGGAAGGGGCUGGAGCCCCAGGCCGGGGGGCCUCGGAAGGGCUCCCCAGGAUGUGUACUCGUUCUCUCACGGCCCUGAGUGAGCCCCGCACGCCCGGACCCCCAGGCCUGACCACCACCCCUGCACCCCCAGACAAACUGGGGGGCAAGCAGCGAGCCGCCUUCAAGUCGGGCAAGCGGGUGGGGAAGCCCUCACCCAAGGCUGCCUCCAGCCCCAGCAACCCGGCCGCCCUGCCUGUGGCCUCCGACAGCAGCCCGAUGGGCUCCAAGACCAAGGAGACAGACUCACCCAGCACGCCUGGCAAGGACCAGCGCUCCAUGAUCCUUCGGUCACGCACCAAAACCCAGGAGAUCUUCCACUCCAAGCGGCGGAGGCCCUCUGAGGGCCGGCUCCCCAACUGCCGUGCCACCAAGAAGCUCCUCGACAACAGCCACUUGCCCGCCACAUUCAAGGUCUCCAGCAGCCCCCAGAAGGAGGGCAGGGUGAGCCAGCGGGCAAGGGUCCCCAAACCUGGUGCAGGCAGCAAGCUCUCUGACCGGCCCCUCCAUGCGCUCAAAAGGAAGUCGGCCUUCAUGGCGCCGGUCCCCACCAAGAAGCGGAACCUGGUCUUGCGGAGCCGCAGCAGCAGCAGCAGCAACGCCAGUGGCAAUGGGGGAGAUGGGAAGGAGGAGAGGCCUGAGGGUUCCCCCACCCUCUUCAAGAGGAUGUCUUCUCCCAAGAAAGCCAAGCCCACCAAGGGCAAUGGCGAGCCUGCCACAAAGCUCCCACCCCCGGAGACCCCCGAUGCCUGCCUCAAGCUCGCCUCUCGGGCAGCCUUCCAGGGGGCCAUGAAGACCAAGGUGCUGCCACCCCGGAAGGGCCGGGGCCUGAAGCUGGAAGCCAUCGUGCAGAAGAUCACCUCGCCCAGCCUCAAGAAGUUCGCAUGUAAAGCGCCAGGGGCCUCUCCUGGUAAUCCUCUGAGCCCAUCCCUUUCCGACAAAGACCGUGGGCUCAAGGGUGCUGGGGGCAGCCCAGUGGGGGUGGAAGAAGGCCUGGUAAAUGUGGGCACCGGGCAGAAGCUCCCAACUUCUGGGGCUGAUCCGUUAUGCAGAAAUCCAACCAACAGAUCCUUAAAAGGCAAACUCAUGAACAGUAAGAAACUGUCUUCUACUGACUGUUUCAAAACCGAGGCCUUCACAUCCCCGGAGGCCCUGCAGCCUGGGGGGACUGCCCUGGCGCCUAAGAAGAGGAGCCGGAAAGGCCGGGCAGGGGCCCAUGGACUCUCCAAAGGCCCGCUGGAGAAGCGGCCCUAUCUUGGCCCGGCUCUGCUCCUGACUCCCCGAGACAGGGCCAGUGGCACACAAGGGGCCAGUGAGGACAACUCUGGUGGAGGAGGCAAGAAGCCAAAGAUGGAGGAGCUGGGCCUGGCCUCCCAGCCCCCGGAGGGCAGGCCCUGCCAGCCCCAGACAAGGGCACAGAAACAGCCAGGCCACACCAACUACAGCAGCUAUUCCAAGCGGAAGCGCCUCACUCGGGGCCGGGCCAAGAACACCACCUCUUCACCCUGUAAGGGGCGUGCCAAGCGACGACGACAGCAGCAGGUGCUGCCCCUGGAUCCCGCAGAGCCUGAAAUCCGCCUCAAGUACAUUUCCUCUUGCAAGCGGCUGAGGUCAGACAGCCGGACCCCCGCCUUCUCACCCUUCGUGCGGGUGGAGAAGCGAGACGCGUUCACCACCAUAUGCACUGUUGUCAACUCCCCUGGAGAUGCGCCCAAGCCCCACAGGAAGCCUUCCUCCUCUGCCUCCUCUUCCUCAUCCUCGUCCUCGUUCUCCUUGGAUGCAGCCGGGGCCUCCCUGGCCACACUCCCUGGAGGCUCCAUCCUGCAGCCGCGGCCCUCCUUGCCCCUCUCCUCCACGAUGCACUUGGGGCCUGUGGUUUCCAAGGCCCUGAGUACCUCUUGCCUUGUUUGCUGCCUCUGCCAAAACCCGGCCAACUUCAAGGACCUUGGGGACCUCUGUGGGCCCUACUACCCUGAACACUGCCUCCCCAAAAAGAAGCCAAAACUCAAGGAGAAGGUGCGGCCAGAAGGCACCUGUGAGGAGGCCUCGCUGCCGCUUGAGAGAACACUCAAAGGUCCCGAGUGUGCAGCUGCCGCCACUGCCGGGAAGCCCCCCAGGCCUGACGGCCCAGCUGACCCGGCCAAGCAGGGCCCACUGCGCACCAGUGCCCGGGGCCUGUCCCGGAGGCUGCAGAGCUGCUACUGCUGUGAUGGCCGGGAGGAUGGGGGCGAGGAGGCAGCCCCAGCCGACAAGGGUCGCAAACAUGAGUGCAGCAAGGAGGCUCCGGCAGAGCCCGGCGGGGAGGCCCAGGAGCACUGGGUGCAUGAGGCCUGUGCCGUGUGGACCGGCGGCGUCUACCUGGUGGCCGGGAAGCUCUUUGGGCUGCAGGAGGCCAUGAAGGUGGCCGUGGACAUGAUGUGUUCCAGCUGCCAAGAAGCCGGGGCCACCAUUGGGUGCUGCCACAAAGGAUGCCUCCACACCUACCACUACCCGUGUGCCAGCGAUGCAGGUUGCAUAUUCAUCGAAGAGAACUUUUCUUUGAAAUGUCCCAAACAUAAGAGGCUGCCGUAGUAAUCCACCCCAACGGCCGGAGGAGCCGCCGGAGCCCGCCUGCCCGCCCGCCGCCGAAGGAGAGGAGCCGCCUGCGCAGCCCCCGGGCCUUUGAGCUGCUCCCAGCGCUGGUCCAGAGCCGAUCCUUGAUCCGGGUCCCGGAUCGUGGAUCCGGCCGCCUAGGGCUCAGACUUGCGGCCCCGGGUUGGGAGGAAAACCCGUUCCGGAGCCGCCUGCUCCCGGAACCGGACGGCACAGGGCGUUCUUGCCCACCCCAGGGGCCAGGCUUGCGGAGGGGGAGCCCGCGGAGCGGCCAGACUCCCCGGGGCGCUCAGCCUCCGGCGAGGGUGGGAGACGGCUUUGUCCUGGGGACACUUUCCCUCUGGAAUCUCAAGACGACGUGGCACACAUUCCACGUGGGUGCUGCCGCCACCCCAGUCGGUCGUGGCGUGCAGCUGGGAGCCCUGGGCUUGGGGGUGGGGGUCGAAACAGUACUGGAAGAGGCGGAGGGCGGCUCCUAGCUCCGUGGACUAGGCGGGGGAGAAAGGAAGCCUUUCUGAGAGCGGGCUAGGCCGGCACUGGAGAGGCCGGAGCCUUUGGAACAAACCGUGCGGAACGCGUCCAGGGGCCUUCCCGCCCAGCCUUUGCCAGAUCUCUCGUGCGGUUCGGGCAAAGCCGGGGUAGACCUGGGCUAUGCUCAGUUAGGGGUUGCGGGAUCCCCGAGUGUGGGCGGGACUGGGACACCCUUUGGCCUCUGUUUGUCCCCUUUCCAGUCCUCCACCCCACCCCUGGAGCCCAGCCUGGGAGCGCAAAACCCAAGAAGCGGCCAGAACGCACCUCCGGCUCCGGCGGACGCGCGACCGUUGUGCACCACCAGGGACCGCCGCGCCUACUCUGCACGGGAGCAGGGACAGCGCUAGAUUUCGUGUACAAAACCUGUGUACCCCUCUAUAUAUAUGUUACAUAGAAUGUAUAUAUGUUGGGAACAUGCUCGCUUCUCCCGUGUGUCGCCGCCGUGCGUCGUGCGCCCGCAACAGAGCCCCAACCGGGCCUUUGCCGGGUAAGGGGCUACCGCGACGCCACUUGUCCACGCAGCCACCACCGGCCCGGGCCAGUCCCUGCCAGUCCGUCCGCCUGUCCGUCCGUGUCCUCAGCUCUGUCCACGCUUCGAUAGGCCUGACGCAGCCCCCAGCCCAGGGCCGCCCUAGCAACUUCCUGUACAUAUGACUGUAAAAUGGUAAACGUGUGUAUUAUAUCUGGCCUCGUUAUAUAGUGUAUAUAUAUGUAUACAUAUACAUAUAUAUAAUAUAUAUGAAGACUGUAAAUGUUAAGACGACUAGUGUUCUUAUUAGUAUAUUGCUUCACACUGAAGAUUGUGUGUAUCGAGCUGUUUCUAAAAGAUGUUUAUUUUCCUUAAGAGUAAAAAACAGUCAUUGCAUUCAGAAAAAAAAAAAAAAAAAAGUCAAUAAAGAUACAACGAUUGUUUUGGAAAA